CUCCCCCGGCCGUAAUGGCCGAGUGUGUGCGCCAGAGCGCGGCUCGCACCCCGCCCGCCGCCGCCGCCGCGCCCGCACCCUCGCACUCACACACUCUCUCAUACACACACACACACACACACACACACAAAGGGAAGGAGCCAUAUUCUCGCUCGCGCUCGCCCUCGCGGCGGCGGCGGCGCAGGCGGAGAAGACGCGCAGCGGCCAUUCCGUGCGCGCCGGCCCCGGCGGCCGCGGGCGGAGCCAGCCCCCAUUUCGAGCGGGGCUUCUCCCUGCGCCGAGCCUGACAAAAUGGGGGCGGCGGCGGCGCGGGCCUGCAGGGCCUGCCGGGCGCACGUGGCGGCCUCGGGCCUGGGAGCCGGGCCGCGUCCUCUCUCCUCGGCCGCGCGGCCACCGGCGAAGUUCUAGGGGCGGGGGGCUCGCCCCGCGCAGGAGUCACCCCAACUUUCACGGCUCCAAAAAAUACUUCCCGAGUUGGGGGAGGGGGCCACCGAGCCACGAGCAGGAGUGGCUUUUGUCCCUCAUCCUUGUUUACUCGGAGAAACUUCAGACCGGACGUGUUUAGUCAGAACAGAAAUACAUCUCAGGGCCAAACCGAUAGGAAACGAGGCUGCCUCGCGGUGGCACCGCCACCCCCCAACCGGGUUCCGAGCACCGGAGCUGGCUGCUGCUCCCUCUUUGGAGCAAAGUUUUAUGCAAAGAGGGUGUUUUUUGAAACUUUCGAAAAAUAACUAAACAUGGGCAAAGGAGAUCCUAAGAAGCCGAGAGGCAAAAUGUCAUCAUAUGCAUUUUUUGUGCAAACUUGUCGGGAGGAGCAUAAGAAGAAGCACCCAGAUGCUUCAGUCAACUUCUCAGAGUUUUCUAAGAAGUGCUCAGAGAGGUGGAAGACCAUGUCUGCUAAAGAGAAAGGAAAAUUUGAAGAUAUGGCAAAAGCGGACAAGGCCCGUUAUGAAAGAGAAAUGAAAACCUAUAUCCCUCCCAAAGGGGAGACAAAAAAGAAGUUCAAGGAUCCCAAUGCACCCAAGAGGCCUCCUUCGGCCUUCUUCCUCUUCUGCUCUGAGUAUCGCCCAAAAAUCAAAGGAGAACAUCCUGGCCUGUCCAUUGGUGAUGUUGCGAAGAAACUGGGAGAGAUGUGGAAUAACACUGCUGCAGAUGACAAGCAGCCUUAUGAAAAGAAGGCUGCGAAGCUGAAGGAAAAAUAUGAAAAGUUCUAGUUAUUUCUGGAGUUGCUGUGGAUCUACAGAUACGUGAUAUUUUGGUAUAACUAGAAUCUUGAUUUCUUUCAUAAAGUUCUGCCAUGUUCUAUUUCUUUCCUUAAUGUUUUUUUCUUCCCUACUGUUUUAUCCUCCCUUUGCUUUGGAAGGAUAUUGCUGCAUAUCGAGCUAAAGGAAAGCCUGAUGCAGCAAAAAAGGGAGUUGUCAAGGCUGAAAAAAGCAAGAAAAAGAAGGAAGAGGAGGAAGAUGAGGAAGAUGAAGAGGAUGAGGAGGAGGAGGAAGAUGAAGAAGAUGAAGAUGAAGAAGAAGAUGAUGAUGAUGAAUAAGUUGGUUCUAGCGCAGUUUUUUUUUUCUUGUCUAUAAAGCAUUUAACCCCCCUGUACACAACUCACUCCUUUUAAAGAAAAAAAUUGAAAUGUAAGGCUGUGUAAGAUUUGUUUUUAAACUGUACAGUGUCUUUUUUUGUAUAGUUAACACACUACCGAAUGUGUCUUUAGAUAGCCCUGUCCUGGUGGUAUUUUCAAUAGCCACUAACCUUGCCUGGUACAGUAUGGGGGUUGUAAAUUGGCAUGGAAAUUUAAAGCAGGUUCUUGUUGGUGCACAGCACAAAUUAGUUAUAUAUGGGGAUGGUAGUUUUUUCAUCUUCAGUUGUCUCUGAUGCAGCUUAUACGAAAUAAUUGUUGUUCUGUUAACUGAAUACCACUCUGUAAUUGCAAAAAAAAAAAAAAAGUUGCAGCUGUUUUGUUGACAUUCUGAAUGCUUCUAAGUAAAUACAAUUUUUUUUAUUAGUAUUGUUGUCCUUUUCAUAGGUCUGAAAUUUUUCUUCUUGAGGGGAAGCUAGUCUUUUGCUUUUGCCCAUUUUGAAUCACAUGAAUUAUUACAGUGUUUAUCCUUUCAUAUAGUUAGCUAAUAAAAAGCUUUUGUCUACACACCCUGCAUAUCAUAAUGGGGGUAAAGUUAAGUUGAGAUAGUUUUCAUCCAUAACUGAACAUCCAAAAUCUUGAUCAGUUAAGAAAUUUCACAUAGCCCACUUACAUUUACAAACUGAAGAGUAAUCAAUCUACUCAAAGCAUGGGAUUAUUAGAAUCAAACAUUUUGAAAGUCUGUCCUUGAAGGACUAAUAGAAAAGUAUGUUCUAACCUUUACAUGAGGACUCUAUUCUUUAACUCCCAUUACCAUGUAAUGGCAGUUAUAUUUUGCAGUUCCCACAUUAAAGAAGACCUGAGAAUGUAUCCCCAAAAGCGUGAGCUUAAAAUACAAGACUGCCAUAUUAAAUUUUUUGUUGACAUUAGUCUCAGUGAAGACUAUGAAAAUGCUGGCUAUAGAUGUCUUUUCCCAUUUAUCUAAAUAUGGACUGCUCAGGAAACGAGACUUUCCAUUACAAGUAUUUUUAAUUAAUUGGGCCAGCUUUUCAAACAAAGAUGCCACAUUCAAAAUAGGGUAUAUUUUCCUAUAUUACGGUUUGCCCCUUUAUAAAUCCAAGUAGAUAGGAAGAAAGAAGACAAACUUUGCAUCUCAGUAUGAAUUAUUCAAUUUAUUUGAAUGAUUUUUCUUUACAAAACAAACUCAUUCAUUAGUCAUGUUUAUCUGCUUAGGAGUUUAGGGAACAAUUUGGCAAUUUUGUGGUUUUCGAGAUUAUCGUUUUCUUAAAGUGCCAGUAUUUUAAAAUAGCGUUCUUGUAAUUUUACACGCUUUUGUGAUGGAGUGCUGUUUUGUUAUAUAAUUUAGACUUGGAUUCUUUCCAUUUGCAUUUGUUUAUGUAAUUUCAGGAGGAAUACUGAACAUCUGAGUCCUGGAUGAUACUAAUAAACUAAUAAUUGCAGAGGUUUUAAAUACUAGUUAAAUGGCUUUCACUUAAGAACUUAAGAUUUUGUUACAUAUUUUUAAAUCUUGUUUCUAAUAAUACCUCUUAGCAGUACCUUUUAAAUAAGUAUAAGGGAUGGCAAAGUUUUUCCCUUUAAAAAUACUCACUUUAUGCUUAUAAAUAGGUUAAUGGGCUGAUAAAAGGUUUUGUCAAACAUUGCAAGUAUUCGGUGCUAUAUAUAAAGGAGGAAAAACUAGUUUUACUUUCAGAAUGAUUUAAACAAGAUUUUUAAAAACAAGAUACAUGCAAGCGAACAGCAGGGUUAGUGAUAGGCUGCAAUUGUGUCGAACAUCAGAUUUUUUGUUAAGAGGAGCAAAUGACUCAAUCUGAUUUAGAUGGAAGUUUCUACUGUAUAGAAAUCACCAUUAAUCACCAACAUUAAUAAUUCUGAUCCAUUUAAAAUGAAUUCUGGCUCAAGGAGAAUUUGUAACUUUAGUAGGUACGUCAUGACAACUACCAUUUUUUUAAGAUGUUGAGAAUGGGAACAGUUUUUUUAGGGUUUAUUCUUGACCACAGAUCUUAAGAAAAUGGACAAAACCCCUCUUCAAUCUGAAGAUUAGUAUGGUUUGGUGUUCUAACAGUAUCCCCUAGAAGUUGGAUGUCUAAAACUCAAGUAAAUGGAAGUGGGAGGCAAUUUAGAUAAGUGUAAAGCCUUGUAACUGAAGAUGAUUUUUUUUAGAAAGUGUAUAGAAACUAUUUUAAUGCCAAGAUAGUUACAGUGCUGUGGGGUUUAAAGACUUUGUUGACAUCAAGAAAAGACUAAAUCUAUAAUUAAUUGGGCCAACUUUUAAAAUGAAGAUGCUUUUUAAAACUAAUGAACUAAGAUGUAUAAAUCUUAGUUUUUUUGUAUUUUAAAGAUAGGCAUAUGGCAUAUUGAUUAACGAGUCAAAUUUCCUAACUUUGCUGUGCAAAGGUUGAGAGCUAUUGCUGAUUAGUUACCACAGUUCUGAUGAUCGUCCCAUCACAGUGUUGUUAAUGUUUGCUGUAUUUAUUAAUUUUCUUAAAGUGAAAUCUGAAAAAUGAAAUUUGUGUGUCCUGUGUACCCGAGGGGUAAUGAUUAAAUGAUAAAGAUAAGAAAAGCGCCCAUGUAACACAAACUGCCAUUCAACAGGUAUUUCCCUUACUACCUAAGGAAUUGUAACCAUUGCUCAGACAUUGUAGGAUUUAACUAUGUUGAAAACUACAGGAGAGGCCGGGCGCAGUGGCUCACGCCUGUAAUCCCAGCACUUUGGGAGGCCAAGGCGGGCAGAUCACGAGGUCAGGAGAUUGAGACCAUCCUGGCUAACGUGGUGAAACCCCGCCUCUACUAAAAAUACAAAAAAUUAGCCAAGCGUGGUGCUGGGCGCCUGUAGUCCCAGUAACUCAGGAGGCUGAGGCAGGAGAAUGGCGUGAACCCGGGAGGCGGAGGUUGCAGUGAGCCGAGAUUGUGCCACUGCACUCCAGCCUGGGUGACAGAGCAAGACUCCAUCUCAAAAAAAAAAAAAAAACACAGGAGAGACAACUGGUUUUUGAAUGAAAUACAUGGGUACUGCCUUGCUUGACAUCACAUAGUCCUUGAUGAAAGUUCACAUUUAGGUCUGCUUGGUACAAUACGCCUCCUAAAAAGGUCCUUGAUGAAAGUUCACAUUUAGGUCUGCUUGGUACAACACGCCUCCUGAAAGGGUCUGAUAGCUUUCAGUAGCAGUAAGACACUUGCAUGUGAUGGUAAGGUAUCUGCAAAUUUGCACACACCGUACACAGCUUAAGUCUUAGAAUUAACUUGCUAAAAUGUGAGCCUUUGGUAAUUAGGCUGUUUUAUUAGGGAGUGUGAUAAUAUUUGAAUUUCUUUUCAUAUUUGUGCUUUGUGUCAUUUUCAAAUGACCCUUGAAAUGUAUUUUAAAAGUAGAUAAAAGCCAGAAAGUGAUUUGAUUGUCUAUCCAGCAAAAGAUGGUGGUUCAUUUUCUUGUCCUCUUAAUACCAAGGCAGUGCUAAUAACACUUGCCACAACUUGGGAAAUUCCAUGGGUCUAUGCCACAUUGCUCCCAGAGUAAUGAGGCAAAAUAGUGCUCUGUUAUAGAAUUGCUUGUUUCACGAUACAUCAUGACAGAUAACCAUACAACAUGGAAUGACACAAACAUAAUAUGCCACACUCCAGAAUAUGUAAUGCUCGUCUUCCAGGGGGGUUCAGUCUAAGGUAAUCUCUACCAGGAAGAAAUGCUAGAUGACUUUAGACAUGUGCAUUGGUUUGGACCUUCUAAUUAGUGGAAUUUUUACUUAUUUUGACAUGAGAGAUUACAUAGAAUCUCUAUGUUGCCCAGGUUGGUCUCCAAAUCUGCUCAAACAAUCCUCCCGCCUCAGUUUCUCAAGUAGCUGGGAUUACAGGGACACACCACUGUGCUUAGCUUAAAUAGUUGAAUUUAUUGGGCAUCCACUGAAAAGAAGGAAGUAGGAAUAAAAUCUGCAAUAGUAUGACUAAACCUGUAAGUGAGCAUGAGCAGUGGUGGGCAAGGGUAUGCAGACUCUGGAAUCCAGAAAUAGAAAGUCAGUGGAAAGCCAGGCACAGUGGCUCACACUUAUAAUCCCAGCACUUUGGGAGGCCGAGGUGGGAGGAUCACUUGAGGCCAGGAGUUUGACACUAGCCUGGGCAACAUAGUGAGGCCUUGUCUACUAGAAAUAAAUAAUUUUGCAGAUAUACUAAAUACCAUUUUAAAAAUAAGUGGAAAAGGGAUUAGAGAGAUCCUUGUAAAUUAUGUACUCAUAUUCAUUGUUCUCUUUAGUCACAUAAUUCAGUCAUGUACGUGACAUUCCACAGUAUGGUGCUCCAUAAUACAUAUUUUUUCUUUUUUCGAUCUCACUUGUAUAUGAUCCAUAAUAUUUUUCAUCAUUCCCUUACUGAUGGACAUUUAGAUUGUUUCCUAUUUUUUGCUGUUUAACAGUACUGCGCUGAACAUCUGUACAUUUCUCUCAGGCAUGUGUGGGUCUUCAGAUACCUCAAAAGUAGAACUGCUGAGUCAAAAGACAUUUGCAUUUAACAUUUUGGAAGAUGUUGAUAAAUUGCACCCCACCACCCCCCCCCCCCGCCCACAAAAGCUGUUAUUUAUGCUGUGAAACAUUUUAACAAUGAUUUUGCAAUUAA